GACAGGCUGCGCCCGCCCGCGCCCGGGGUGAUGCAGUUGCCCCCCGCGCUGUGCGCCCGCCUCGCUGCGGGGCCCGGGGCGGCGGAGCCGCUGCCUGUAGAGCGGGAUCCCGCGGCUGGGGCCGCGCCCUUUCGCUUCGUUGCGCGCCCCGUGCGCUUCCCGCGGGAGCACCAGUUCUUCGAGGAUGGGGACGUGCAGCGCCACCUCUACCUCCAGGACGUGAUCAUGCAGGUGGCCGACGUGCCUGAGAAGCCCAGGGUGCCCGCGUUUGCCUGCCAGGUGGCCGGCUGCUGCCAGGUGUUCGAUGCCCUGGACGACUACGAGCACCACUACCACACGCUGCACGGAAAUGUUUGCUCCUUUUGCAAGCGGGCCUUCCCUUCCGGACACCUGCUGGACGCCCACAUCCUGGAGUGGCACGAUUCGCUCUUCCAGAUCCUGUCUGAGAGGCAGGACAUGUAUCAGUGCUUGGUAGAAGGCUGCACAGAGAAGUUCAAGACCAGCAGAGACCGGAAGGAUCACAUGGUGAGGAUGCACCUGUACCCCGCGGACUUCCGGUUUGAUAAGCCAAAGAAAAGCAGAAGCCCAGCCUCAGCAGAAGCCCCAGGGGACAGUGGAGAGCGGUCAGAAGGGGAGGCCAUGGAAAUCUGCUCUGAGCCUGUGGCAGCCUCCCCUGCACCGGCAGGUGAGAGGCGGAUCUACAGACAUAGGCUCCUCCUGGUCACCAGCCUGGUGGUUGUGCUGCUGUGGGAGGCAGGUGCAGUCCCAGCACCCAAGGUCCCUAUCAAGAUGCAAGUCAAACACUGGCCCUCAGAGCAGGACCCAGAGAAGGCCUGGGGCGCCCGUGUGGUGGAGCCUCCGGAGAAGGACGACCAGCUGGUGGUGCUGUUCCCUGUCCAGAAGCCGAAACUCUUGACCACCGAGGAGAAGCCACGAGGUCAGGGCAGGGGCCCCAUCCUUCCAGGCACCAAGGCCUGGAUGGAGACCGAGGACACCCUGGGCCAUGUCCUGAGUCCCGAGCCCGACCAUGACAGCCUGUACCACCCUCCGCCUGAGGAGGACCAGGGCGAGGAGAGGCCCCGGUUGUGGGUGAUGCCAAAUCACCAGGUGCUCCUGGGACCGGAGGAAGACCAAGACCACAUCUACCACCCCCAGUAGGGCUCCAGGGGCCAUCACUGCCCCCGCCCUGUCCCAAGGCCCAGGCUGUUGGGACUGGGACCCUCCCUACCCUGCCCCAGCUAGACAAAUAAACCCCAGCAGGCCGGGCGCGGUGGCUCACCUCUGUAAUCCCAGCACUUUUAGAGGCCGAGGCAGGCGGAUCACCUGAAAUCAGGAGUUCCAGACCAGCCUGGGCAACAUGGUGAAACCCCGUCUCUACUAAAAAUACAAAAAUUAGCCGGG